AGACGGCUCCGGACGGGACCGCGAGCACAGGCCGCUCCGCGGGCGCUUCGGAUCCUCGCGGGACCCCACCCUCUCCCAGCCUGCCCAGCCCGCUGCAGCCGCCAGCGCGCCCCGUCGGCAGCUCUCCAUCUGCACGUCUCUCCGUGAACCCCGUGAGCGGUGUGCAGCCACCAUGUUCAGCUGGCUGAAGCGGGGCGGGGCACGGGGCCAGCAGCCCGAGGCCAUCCGCACGGUGACCUCGGCCCUCAAGGAGCUGUACCGCACGAAGCUGCUGCCGCUGGAGGAGCACUACCGCUUUGGGGCCUUCCACUCGCCGGCCCUGGAGGACGCAGACUUCGACGGCAAGCCCAUGGUGCUGGUGGCCGGCCAGUACAGCACGGGCAAGACCAGCUUCAUCCAGUACCUGCUGGAGCAGGAGGUGCCCGGCUCCCGCGUGGGGCCUGAGCCCACCACCGACUGCUUUGUGGCCGUCAUGCACGGGGACACUGAGGGCACCGUGCCCGGCAACGCCCUCGUCGUGGACCCGGACAAGCCCUUCCGCAAACUCAACCCUUUCGGAAACACCUUCCUCAACAGGUUCAUGUGUGCCCAGCUCCCUAAUCAGGUCCUGGAGAGCAUCAGCAUCAUCGACACCCCGGGUAUCCUGUCGGGUGCCAAGCAGAGAGUGAGCCGCGGCUACGACUUCCCGGCCGUGCUGCGCUGGUUCGCGGAGCGCGUGGACCUCAUCAUCCUGCUCUUUGAUGCGCACAAGCUGGAGAUCUCGGACGAGUUCUCAGAGGCCAUCGGCGCGUUGCGGGGCCAUGAGGACAAGAUCCGCGUGGUGCUCAACAAGGCCGACAUGGUGGAGACGCAGCAGCUGAUGCGCGUCUACGGCGCGCUCAUGUGGGCGCUGGGCAAGGUGGUGGGCACGCCCGAGGUGCUGCGCGUCUACAUCGGCUCCUUCUGGUCCCAGCCCCUCCUCGUGCCCGACAACCGGCGCCUCUUCGAGCUGGAGGAGCAGGACCUCUUCCGCGACAUCCAGGGCCUGCCCCGGCACGCAGCCUUGCGCAAGCUCAACGACCUGGUGAAGAGGGCCCGGCUGGUGCGAGUUCACGCUUACAUCAUCAGCUACCUGAAGAAGGAGAUGCCCUCUGUGUUUGGGAAGGAGAACAAGAAGAAGCAGCUGAUCCUCAAACUGCCCGUCAUCUUUGCGAAGAUUCAGCUGGAACAUCACAUCUCCCCUGGGGACUUUCCUGAUUGCCAGAAAAUGCAGGAGCUGCUGAUGGCGCACGACUUCACCAAGUUUCACUCGCUGAAGCCGAAGCUGCUAGAGGCACUGGACGAGAUGCUGACGCACGACAUCGCCAAGCUCAUGCCCCUGCUGCGGCAGGAGGAGCUGGAGAGCACCGAGGUGGGCGUGCAGGGGGGCGCUUUUGAGGGCACCCACAUGGGCCCGUUUGUGGAGCGGGGACCUGACGAGGCCAUGGAGGACGGCGAGGAGGGCUCGGACGACGAGGCCGAGUGGGUGGUGACCAAGGACAAGUCCAAAUACGACGAGAUCUUCUACAACCUGGCGCCUGCCGACGGCAAGCUGAGCGGCUCCAAGGCCAAGACCUGGAUGGUGGGGACCAAGCUCCCCAACUCAGUGCUGGGGCGCAUCUGGAAGCUCAGCGAUGUGGACCGCGACGGCAUGCUGGAUGAUGAGGAGUUCGCGCUGGCCAGCCACCUCAUCGAGGCCAAGCUGGAAGGCCACGGGCUGCCCGCCAACCUGCCCCGUCGCCUGGUGCCACCCUCCAAGCGACGCCACAAGGGCUCCGCCGAGUGAGCCGGCCCCCCUCCCAUGGCCCUGCUGUGGCUCCCCAGCUCCAGUCGGCUGCACGCACACCCCUGCUCCGGCUCACACACGCCCUGCCUGCCCUCCCUGCCCAGCUGUAAGGACCGGGGGUCUCCCUCCUCACUACCGCCAGACACCCCGGUGGAAGCAUUUAGAGGGGACCACGGGAGGGACAAGGCUUCUCUGUCCGCCCUUCACACCUCCAGCCUCACGUUCACUUAGGCACAUCACACACACACUGGCACACGCAGGCAUCCAUCCAUCCGUCAUUCAUUCAAAUAUUUAUUGAGCACCUACUAUGUGCCCAGCCCUGUUCUAGGCACUGGGCAUUACCAUAGAGAACAAAAUAGACAAAUACAUCUGCCCUCAUGGAAGGUGACGUUCCCAGGAGAGGGCACCUACACAGUCACGCAAACACACACUAAUUCCUGGCAGGGCCCCCAGCCCCUCCCCUGGCUGAGCAGCCCUGUGGCUGAAAUGACUAGCAGAUAAACAGACCCCCUUCUGCUCCGCUUCCUCCUGCCCAGCCAGGCAACACCCUCAACCGGCUCCAUCACAUCCUCAGGUCUCGGGACCAUGGGGGGCUCAGAGGGGAGACACACCUACUGCUUCCUCAGAUGGGCCCCUCCGCAGCCCCUUCCCUUGCUCGGGGAAAGCCCCCAAUUCUGCCCACACCCAUUUAUUUCCUUCCUUCCUUCCUUCUUUUCUUUCCUUCCUUCCUUCUUUUUUGUUUUUGCCCCCAAUUCUGCCCAUACCCAUUUCUUUCUUUCCUUCCUUCCUUCUUUUUUGUUUUUGCCCCCAGUUCUGUCCACACCCCUUCCCUUUCCUGUCCUGUCCUUUCUUUCUUUUUUGAUAGAAUCUUGCUCUGUCGCCCAGGCUGGAGUGCAGUGGUGAGAUCUCAGCUCACUGCAACCUCCACCUCCUGGGUUGAAGUGAUUCUCGUGCCUCAGCCUCCUGAGUAGCUGGGACUGCAGGCACGCGCCACCACGCCCAGCUAAUUUUUGUAUUUGAGUAGAGACGGGGUUUCACCAUGUUGGCCAGGCUGGUCUCGAACUCCGCAUCUCAGGUGAUCUGCUCGCCUUGGCCUCCCAAAGUGAUGGGAUUACAGGCAUGAGCCACCGUGCCCGGCUUCACACCCAUUUCUUUAAAAAGGAUCCCGUAGCAGGCAGAAAAGCCCCUUCCAUCCUGCUCCUCUGAUACUGUGCCCCCUUGGAGAUAUUUCCGUCCUCCACCCACGUGUCUGUGGCUGGAACUGCCCAGCCUGCUCCUGGCCCCCUGGAAGCCUCCCCACAGCUGGUAAUCUGGACUUAAGGAUUGCUGGGCCACCGCCUCUCUGCCUACCACCAUUCCAUAUUUAAGUGGAGCCCCUACGUAGAAAGGCCCCGGGGCUUUAUUUUAGUCUCCUUUUCAGGGAUGUCGUGGGCGGGGGAGGGGGUUCUUGGUGCUACAGCCCUCUCCCCACCCCUAAAGGGACGCCGACGCUGUUUGCUGCCUUCACCACAUAUUAGUGCUUGACCCUGGCAGGGGACCCCAUGGAAAAGAUGGGGAAGAGCAAAAUACAUGGAGACGACGCACCCUCCAGGAUGCUCGCUGGGAUUCCCACGCCCACCACUGUCCCCCACCCCAUGGCUGGGAGGGGCCUCUGAACGGAACAGUGUCCCCACAGAGCGAAUAAAGCCAAGGCUUCUUCCCA